GAUCCACCCUCAAUCUACCAGAAUCAUGGGCUGCUGUGGCUGCUCCGGAGGCUGUGGCUCCGGCUGUGGGGGUUGUGGCUCCGGCUGUGGGGGCUGUGGCUCCGGCUGUGGGGGCUAUGGCUCUGGCUGUGGGGGCUGUGGCUCCAGCUGCUGUGUGCCCGUCUGCUGCUGCAAGCCCGUGUGCUGCUGUGUGCCAGCCUGUUCCUGCUCCAGCUGUGGCUCCUGUGGGGGCUCCAAGGGGGACUGUGGCUCUUGUGGGGGCUCCAAAGGGGGCUGUGGUUCCUGUGGGGGCUCCAAGGGGGGCUGUGGCUCCUGUGGGGGCUCCAAGGGGGGCUGUGGUUCUUGUGGGGGCUCCAAGGGGGGCUGUGGCUCCUGUGGGGGCUCCAAAGGUGGCUGUGGUUCCUGUGGGGGCUCCAAGGGGGGCUGUGGUUCUUGUGGCUGCUCCCAGUGCAAUUGCUGUAAGCCCUGCUGCUGCUCCUCAGGCUGUGGAUCCUGCUGCCAGUCCAGCUGCUGCAAUCCCUGCUGCUGCCAGUCCAGCUGCUGUGUCCCCGUGUGCUGCCAGUCUAGCUGCUGCAAGCCCUGCUGCUGUCAGUCCAGCUGCUGUGUCCCCGUGUGCUGCCAGUGUAAGAUCUGAGGCUCUGAACCCAGACCUUCAGGUUUCACCUGUUUGGUGAAAGCAUUUGUUAUGAUUUCCCUGAAUUAAUUCAUCCCACGCAUCCUCCCUGAGGCACCUGCCCCUUCUCCAGCUCAUCAUCCAUGCACGCACCUCCUUCCAUGGCUCAGCUCUCCACUGGGCCCUGCCUUCAGCCUCCUCACUCCGGAAAUGCAUGUUUCCUUGAUGCAGGAGGUGGCCUUGCCUGGACGCGGGCACCCAGCCAACUGCCAUGGUGUUCCCUGCACUUGGGUGUGGACCAUCUUCUUCUUCUCCCUCGGCUGACUGAGAUGCAAGGUCUGACCCCACAAGGCCAGGCCAAUGUUGCUCAGUGAUCACUAAGAACCAGCUUCUCAACCACCAUUGGGACCCUGGAUCCUCCAGGGCCGCUCGCUGCCUGUUCUCCAGUGGCCACCUGUGACCAGGAAGGUCUCCUUCCUUCCUGUUGUCUCCAUCUAUUUAAAAACAAUAACAAAGUAAUGAAUGAAUUUCCUUACAAUAAAGCCUCUCAUGUCUGUAAA